AGUCUGGACCUGCCCAAGGACCCCUGCAAUUAGGCCUCCCAUGCAGAGGUCAGUGAGAGCCCAAGCCAAUUGCUCUAGGCCCCGUGGCUGGCUACUUAUGGGGCACUGUCCUGACCAGCUCUGCUAAGAUGCUCCUGGCCCCUCCCUCCACCCCGUCCAGAGGACGGACCCCCAGCGCCGUGGAGAGGCUGGAAGCCGACAAAGCCAAGUAUGUCAAGACGCACCAGGUGAUAGCUAGGCGACAGGAGCCAGCCCUGCGUGGGAGUCCUGGGCCGCUCACGCCGCACCCCUGCAACGAGCUGGGGCCCCCUGCAUCGCCCAGGACGCCCAGGCCGGUCCGCCGGGGAAGCGGCAGGCGGCUGCCGAGGCCUGAUUCCCUCAUCUUCUACCGCCAGAAGCGGGACUGCAAGGCUUCGGUGAACAAAGAGAACGCCAAGGGCCAGGGUCUGGUGCGGCGCCUCUUUCUGGGUGCCCCGCGGGACGCUGCCCCGAGCAGCCCGGCCUCCACAGAGCGACCUGCGGCUUCAGGGGGUUGGGCUGCGCCCCAGGAUGCCCCGGAAGCGGCGGGAAAGCGGGCGCUGUGUCCCACGUGCUCGCUGCCCCUGUCGGAGAAGGAGCGCUUCUUCAACUACUGCGGCCUGGAGCGCGCGCUGGUGGAGGUGCUGGGCGCAGAGCGCUUCUCCCCGCAGAGCUGGGGAGCCGACGCCAGCCCGCAGGCCGGAACUUCGCCGCCGCCCGGCUCCGGGGACGCCAGCGACUGGACAUCCAGCGACAGGGGCGUGGACAGCCCGGGCGGCGCGGGCGGCGGCGGCGGCUCGGAGGCAGCGGGCUCGGCGCGGGACCGGCGCCCCCCGGUGUCGGUGGUGGAGCGCAACGCGCGCGUCAUCCAGUGGCUGUACGGCUGCCAGCGCGCCCGCGGACCGCCGCGCGAGUCCGAGGUGUGACCGCCGCGGCUCCGGACUGGCCCCGGGACUGGCCCCGGGCACGGAAAAGGACACCCCUCUUCUGGCGCGCUGGGUGCCUUUGCGUAAGCCCUUCCUUCUGGAACUCAGUUUCGCGUCUGAACCUUGGGGAGGUGGAACAAGUUGCUGCCGAAGGCCCUUCCCUGCUCCCGCGGCGAAGGGGGAGGGAGAGGCCUCUUGGUCCCUGUGGAGACCCGGUCUGGGGAGUCACGAUUGGGGUGGGAGAUGAGCAAACCUGCUGAAUAAAGUUAAAACGUUAUUUAAAUGGGGAGCUGAGGAAGGAGCAAACGGGUUUUCGCGGUUAAACCCGUGGGUUUUGGAAUGUGUGUUCCCGGCUGUGUGAUCCUGGGCAAGAACUUGACCUCCCUGGACGCAGCGGCACCCCUCGGUUAUUAAGGAGGGAGGAGUAGGGGAUAGAAGUAUUUCAAAAUAGUUGUAAUGCGCAUGGCAAAGUGCCCAGCAUAUAGAAAGUGCUCAAUAAACGAUAACUGCUGUGACUUCUACCGAAUGAGUACUAACACUGUUGUGAUCUCCACUGGCCUCCAGGUCGAUCCAAACUAGAGCUGGGAGCUGGGAAUAAUGCGCUUUGGGAGCCCGAGGAGGCGUCUGCUCCAGAAAUCUGGGCUCCACCAGAUCCUAAAAGGCCCCAUUCCCGGAGUUUUGCUGCCCCAGUUGUGGUCACUGGGUAUGAAGGGCUGAGAUCCAACCUUUCGGACACAAAAAGAAGGGAACCGGGCCGGGCGCGGUGGCUCAGGCCUGUAAUCCCAGCACUUUGGGAGGCUGAGGAGGGUAGAUCACGAGAUCAGGAGUUCGAGACCAGCCUGGCCAACAUGGGCUCUACUAAAAAUACAAAAAUUAGCUGAGCUUGGAGGCGCGCGCCUGUAAUCCCAGCUACUCGGGAGGCUGAGGCAGGAGAAUCGCUUGAAUCCCAGAGGCGGAGGUUGCAGUGAGCCGAGAUCGAGCCAUUGCACUCCAGCCUGGGCAACAGGGCCAGACUCCGUCUCAAAAAAUAAAAAUAAAAAUAAAAAAAGAAAAGAAGGAAACCUUUCCUGCCAGCCGGCAGGCUCCUGCCACUGCCUCCCUUUCCUGCAAGGACACACAAGUUCGCCUAUUUUCAUCACAGGUUCGCACCUCCAAGCCUGCAUCCUUCAUGCACCUCCUUCCUUUGCCUGGGUUGCCGUUCCUUUUCUCUCUGCUCUUCCUUCUCUUUUUUUUUUUUUUUUUUUUUUUUUUUUUUGAGACGGAGUCUCGCUCUGUCGCCCAGGCUGGAGUGCAGUGGCGGGAUCUCGGCUCACUGCAAGCUCCGCCUCCCGGGUUCACGCCAUUCUCCUGCCUCAGCCUCCCAAGUAGCUGGGACUACAGGCGCCCGCCACUACGCCCGGCUAAUUUUUUGUAUUUUUAGUAGAGACGGGGUUUCACCGUUUUAGCCGGGAUGGUCUCGAUCUCCUGACCUCGUGAUCCGCCCGCCUCGGCCUCCCAAAGUGCUGGGAUUACAGGCGUGAGCCACCGCGCCCGGCCCCCUUCUUCCUUCUCGGAGAUAACGUAUAUUCUCCUCCAGGAAGCCGUCCUGAAUGCCCCCAGUCAGCCUCACCUGCUCUGAGCUCCCAAGUACAGUCCUAUUUUUGGGCCUCAAUUUGUCACCUUUUGUGGGACCCGCUGGUACUCUGGGUUCUCUAGUUAAUCUUUGACCUUUUUCCUAGUACAGGGACGGCGCACAUAGUAGGGCCACAGGCACAGUUUGUUGAAUUAAAUGAGGCUGGAGAGGGCGAUGGACGCAGUCCUCUGGAGCUCUCCAACUUCCUGGAAAGUUGUACCUUAAAUAAAAAACCCAUCCUGA